ACUCAUUGGCAGUUACAACUUUGCCAGCACUACAGCCUAAGCUUCCAGAGUGGACACGGAGAAGGGCAUCAGAAAACCAUUCUGGUGAGGUCCACACCCAUAAGUCACCAUGUACAAGGACUGCAUCGAGUCCACUGGAGACUAUUUUCUUCUCUGUGACGCCGAGGGGCCAUGGGGCAUCAUUCUGGAGUCCCUGGCCAUACUUGGCAUCGUGGUCACAAUUCUGCUACUCUUAGCAUUUCUCUUCCUCAUGCGAAAGAUCCAAGACUGCAGCCAGUGGAAUGUCCUCCCCACCCAGCUCCUCUUCCUCCUGAGUGUCCUGGGGCUCUUCGGACUCGCUUUUGCCUUCAUCAUCGAGCUCAAUCAACAAACUGCCCCCGUACGCUACUUUCUCUUUGGGGUUCUCUUUGCUCUCUGUUUCUCAUGCCUCUUAGCUCAUGCCUCCAAUCUAGUGAAGCUGGUUCGGGGUUGUGUCUCCUUCUCCUGGACGACAAUUCUGUGCAUUGCUAUUGGUUGCAGUCUGUUGCAAAUCAUUAUUGCCACUGAGUAUGUGACUCUCAUCAUGACCAGAGGUAUGAUGUUUGUGAAUAUGACACCCUGCCAGCUCAAUGUGGACUUUGUUGUACUCCUGGUCUAUGUCCUCUUCCUGAUGGCCCUCACAUUCUUCGUCUCCAAAGCCACCUUCUGUGGCCCGUGUGAGAACUGGAAGCAGCAUGGAAGGCUCAUCUUUAUCACUGUGCUCUUCUCCAUCAUCAUCUGGGUGGUGUGGAUCUCCAUGCUCCUGAGAGGCAACCCGCAGUUCCAGCGACAGCCCCAGUGGGACGACCCGGUCGUCUGCAUUGCUCUGGUCACCAACGCAUGGGUUUUCCUGCUGCUGUACAUCGUCCCUGAGCUCUGCAUUCUCUACAGAUCGUGUAGACAGGAGUGCCCUUUACAAGGCAAUGCCUGCCCCGUCACAGCCUACCAACACAGCUUCCAAGUGGAGAACCAGGAGCUCUCCAGAGCCCGAGACAGUGAUGGAGCUGAGGAGGAUGUAGCAUUAACUUCAUAUGGUACUCCCAUUCAGCCGCAGACUGUUGAUCCCACACAAGAGUGUUUCAUCCCACAGGCUAAACUAAGCCCCCAGCAAGAUGCAGGAGGAGUAUAAAUCUACAGGAAACACAAGUGGAGAAAACCCAGCAGACCGUCCUGGGUAGCAUAGCCCUGAUAGCCCACGGGGGCCCACAGAGUCACGCUGCCAAUGAAGAGUCAGCAUCCCACCUUCUGUUUCCUAACCCCUCCAUCCACCAGGACCCUCCACCAGAAGACCACCAUUUUGAGCAUAAUUACAAUCUUGCUGGCCACCCU